GUUUAAAAGCAGCGAUCCAUCAGCAACACCAAACUUGAAAUUGAUUUAUGUGGAAAAACUUGGCUUGUCUGCCAUCUAACAAGCCCUGUUGAGUAAAAUAAGCAAGCUUAAAUUUGAUUAGUUGUGUGUCUGCCUGAAACCAUUUAGUAGAGCACUUUAAUUCUGCAUGGUUUUUACAAAACUCAUUAAAAGCUGGACAACAAAAGAAUUCUAUUCUGUAGCUAGUAAUUACAGCUCUUUAUGUGGGAGUGGUAGGCUGCCUUUUCUCCUGGUAUUUGUACACAAAAGCUGGGGAGAGCUUUUCCACUGCCUUCCACAUUCAUUCUCUGUCCAUCUCAGAGAAGCUGAAAAACAGAAUCAAGUCAGCAAGCAGUCUGCAAGCCUAAGGAAGAAAAAGAGCUGACCCAUCCGGCUCUGGAUGGAUAACUGGCAACACCCAAGAUGUCUAUGAUUUUGGCCUUCUGUUUGAGGCUUGUUUAUUUCUUUAAUCAGCAGCUACCAGGACUUAUUUCAUGCAGAGAAAUGACAUAAAGCUCUAGAGGAAGGAGCAUUUCACAUUGGAAGGAGUAGUGAGAAGGGCCUGAUCUGAUAAUAUCAGGAUGGGUGGGAAGGGUCCAUUCCUCAUCAUUCAUGUUCUCCCGGCACAGAGGACUGUGUGGAGGACUCAGGAUUUAGGACCAUACUCAACUGGGGUUUGAUCUCCACUUUGCCCUGCGGUGGCCCCUCUGGUAGCUAUGUGGAUCCUGGGCAGAUUGUCCAUGUUGCUGGGCCUCCGUUGCUUCACUGUAUGACGUCUGCCUCUCAGGGAUGCAGGAAGAUUCAAUUAGGUAGGAGUGGAUGGUCCCCCAGCACGGGGCUUAGCUCUUAGUAACUAGGCAUUCUGGCAAUGGCAGCCAUCAAUAGGAGAGACUAUUGAUUGUUGAGUGAAUAUAAGUGGCAUAAUCCACCAAGUGGAGAUUCUGAGUGAAUGUGGCCACUUUGGACCCAAGACUGCUGCCCCUCUCUGUCCUCUCAUAGGACUAUUAUUUAUUGCCAGUGCUGACCAGCCUUUGUUGGCUACCAUGAUCAUUACCUGCACUCCGAGUGUUUUAACAGAAUUUUCUGAUGCCUCUGGCCUCACCUGCUGCCUUUUAGCCAAGAGGGGUGUGUGUGUAUGUGUGUGUGUGUGUGUGUGUGUGUGUUGGGUGUGUGUUGGGUAGCAGGGUUCUUGGAAGGUCUGGUUUAGCCAUAAUGUUGAUCAUAAAGAGAAAACAAGAAAAUAAAUGCAAAUUAAAUAGUUCGGUGAGCCUUUGUUAUUUCGCCACAUCCAGUAAGUUCUAUCAGUUGAAUGUUGUCUGAAUUACUUAAAAAGUUCUCAGUUGUAAACAGGUAAGAGCACCCAGUGGAGGCCAUGGAGCUAGGCUUAGAGCUUUGCCACCAGCCUUCAGUUCCAUAGCCAUGAACCUGGGAGGGCAAGGAAUCACCCUAGAGGUGAAGGCCAUUCAUCGGUGCUAACCCAAGGUCUCUGAAAAUGAGUUUUAGUUACUCUAUUAUCUAAGUAUCUUUCUUACUGAUAUGUAACUUACCUGGCUGAACAAUUACAUUUUAGAGCUCCAAAUAAAUUUUCAGCCUAUUAUGUCAUUGUCCAAUUACAAGCCUCAUUGUAAUAGCCAUGUUAAAAACAAUAAAGCCGGUGAAAUUGAUUUCAGUGUAUUUCAAAUUAACCUAAUAUAUUCGAAAUAUUAUGUAUGUAUAAAAAUUAUUGAGCUUUUUUCUUUUUUCCACUAAGUCUUUGAGAGCUAGUGUGUAUGUGUGGAUUUGUACUAGCCACUGGUUGAGAGCUCUGUAGCCACACAUGGCAAGUGGGUACCAUAUUGCUUAGCCCAGGCCUAGUAGAAGAUUAAGACUCAGUCAGAGGAAGUAAGGCAGAUCCGUGCUUGGAAUCAGUUCCUCUUGAAGAAGUGCACAGCCAAGCAACACACAAAGCAGAAAUAUUUUGAGCUCUGUAUUCAAAGCAGGAAGAUCUGGGACCAUGUAAGGGGGUUUGGUCUUCAGUUCUCCCUUUGAUCCCUUCCCUGGGUGUGUGCUUUCUUACAGCCUGGAGAGUGGAAGGGAAGAGAGGGGGCUUCCUGGACUCCUUUCCUGUCUCUAGAAAUGACCCCUGCAGCUGUCCUGAAGCUCUCAGGUUAAGCUGAUUGUGUCCAGAGCAGACAGGAGGCGGCCCACUGCCCCACUGUACCCACCCAAGCACUCACCUAAGCUGGCCAUGGAAAUGUGAAUGAAAAGCCUGACCCAGGCCCUCUUGCCCUGCUAACCCAGCAAGGAGGCUCUGACCAGCCAGCCAGCAAGUGACUUUUUCUGUGACAUCUAAGUGGAAUUCAAUGAAUGAUUUCGGAAUCAAGAAUAUGGACCAGGUAGCCCCUGUGGCUAACAGUUACAGAGGGACACUCAAGCGCCAGCCAGCCUUUGACACCUUUGAUGGGUCCCUGUUUGCUGUUUUUCCUUCUCUAAAUGAAGAGCAAACACUGCAAGAAGUGCCAACAGGCUUGGAUUCCAUUUCUCAUGACUCCGCCAACUGUGAAUUGCCUUUGUUAACCCCGUGCAGCAAGGCUGUGAUGAGUCAAGCCUUAAAAGCUACCUUCAGUGGCUUCAAAAAGGAACAGCGGCGCCUGGGCAUUCCAAAGAACCCCUGGCUGUGGAGUGAGCAACAGGUAUGCCAGUGGCUUCUCUGGGCCACCAAUGAGUUCAGUCUGGUGAACGUGAAUCUGCAGAGGUUCGGCAUGAAUGGCCAGAUGCUGUGUAACCUUGGCAAGGAACGCUUUCUGGAGCUGGCACCUGACUUUGUGGGUGACAUUCUCUGGGAACAUCUGGAGCAAAUGAUCAAAGAAAACCAAGAAAAGACAGAAGAUCAAUAUGAAGAAAAUUCACACCUCACCUCCGUUCCUCAUUGGAUUAACAGCAAUACAUUAGGUUUUGGCACAGAGCAGGCGCCCUAUGGAAUGCAGACACAGAAUUACCCCAAAGGCGGCCUCCUGGACAGCAUGUGUCCGGCCUCCACACCCAGCGUACUCAGCUCUGAGCAGGAGUUUCAGAUGUUCCCCAAGUCUCGGCUCAGCUCCGUCAGCGUCACCUACUGCUCUGUCAGUCAGGACUUCCCAGGCAGCAACUUGAAUUUGCUCACCAACAAUUCUGGGACUCCCAAAGACCACGACUCCCCUGAGAACGGUGCGGACAGCUUCGAGAGCUCAGACUCCCUCCUCCAGUCCUGGAACAGCCAGUCGUCCUUGCUGGAUGUGCAACGGGUUCCUUCCUUCGAGAGCUUCGAAGAUGACUGCAGCCAGUCUCUCUGCCUCAAUAAGCCAACCAUGUCUUUCAAGGAUUACAUCCAAGAGAGGAGUGACCCAGUGGAGCAAGGCAAACCAGUUAUACCUGCAGCUGUGCUGGCCGGCUUCACAGGAAGUGGACCUAUUCAGCUGUGGCAGUUUCUCCUGGAGCUGCUAUCAGACAAAUCCUGCCAGUCAUUCAUCAGCUGGACUGGAGACGGAUGGGAGUUUAAGCUCGCCGACCCCGAUGAGGUGGCCCGCCGGUGGGGAAAGAGGAAAAAUAAGCCCAAGAUGAACUACGAGAAGCUGAGCCGGGGCUUACGCUACUAUUACGACAAGAACAUCAUCCACAAGACGUCGGGGAAGCGCUACGUGUACCGCUUCGUGUGCGACCUCCAGAACUUGCUGGGGUUCACGCCCGAGGAACUGCACGCCAUCCUGGGCGUCCAGCCCGACACGGAGGACUGAGGUCGCCGGGACCACCCUGAGCCGGCCCCAGGCUCGUGGACUGAGUGGGAAGCCCAUCCUGACCAGCUGCUCCGAGGACCCAGGAAAGGCAGGAUUGAAAAUGUCCAGGAAAGUGGCCAAGAAGCAGUGGCCUUAUUGCAUCCCAAACCACGCCUCUUGACCAGGCUGCCUCCCUUGUGGCAGCAACGGCACAGCUAAUUCUACUCACAGUGCUUUUAAGUGAAAAUGGUCGAGAAAGAGGCACCAGGAAGCCGUCCUGGCGCCUGGCAGUCCGUGGGACGGGAUGGUUCUGGCUGUUUGAGAUUCUCAAAGGAGCGAGCAUGUCGUGGACACACACAGACUAUUUUUAGAUUUUCUUUUGCCUUUUGCAACCAGGAACAGCAAAUGCAAAAACUCUUUGAGAGGGUAGGAGGGUGGGAAGGAAACAACCAUGUCAUUUCAGAAGUUAGUUUGUAUAUAUUAUUAUAAUCUUAUAAUUGUUCUCAGAAUCCCUUAACAGUUGUAUUUAACAGAAAUUGUAUAUUGUAAUUUAAAAUAAUUAUAUAACUGUAUUUGAAAUAAGAAUUCAGACAUCUGAGGUUUUAUUUCAUUUUUCAAUAGCACAUAUGGAAUUUUGCAAAGAUUUAAUCUGCCAAGGGCCGACUAAGAGAAGUUGUAAAGUAUGUAUUAUUUACAUUUAAUAGACUUACAGGGAUAAGGCCUGUGGGGGGUAAUCCCUGCUUUUUGUGUUUUUUUGUUUGUUUGUUUGUUUGUUUUUGGGGGGUUUUCUUGCCUUGGUUGUCUGGCAAGGACUUUGUACAUUUGGGAGUUUUUAUGAGAAACUUAAAUGUUAUUAUCUGGGCUUAUAUCUGGCCUCUGCUUUCUCCUUUAAUUGUAAAGUAAAAGCUAUAAAGCAGUAUUUUUCUUGACAAAUGGCAUAUGUUUUCCACUUCUUUGCAUGCGUUUAAGUCAGUUUAUACACAAAAUGGAUUUUAUUUUUUAGUUUAACUGUGUUUCUCCGACAGCUCACCUCUCUCUGACCACCCAGCCAUUUCCUUCCUGUGCUCCACGUUCUUCUGUGUGAUUAAAAUAAGAAUAUUAUUUUUGGAAAUAUGCAACUCCUUUUCAGAGAUCAGGAGGGAUUUAUGUAGCAGCUAUUUUUACUGCAAAAGUAAUUCACUGGAAAAAAAAUGUAAUUUGUAAGAAAGCUUUAUUUUUAUCUCAGCUCUAUGUAAAGUUAAAGUUACUGUACAGAGCUGAAGGACGGGGGGCGGUAGGGGUCUUGAUGAAACCUCUUGAACGAAGCACAGUUUGUCCCAUCUUUGUUCACUCGUGUGUCUCAACCAUCUUAAUAGCAUGCUGCUCCUUUUUGCUCAGUGUCCACAGCAAGAUGACGUGAUUCUUAUUUUCUUGGACACAGACUAUUCUGAGGCACAGAGCGGGGACUUAAGAUGGGAAAGAGAAAGCAUCGGAGCCAUUCAUUCGGAGAAAACGUUUUGAUCAAAAUGGAGACUUUUGUAGUCGUUUCAAAAGAGCACCUGAGUCAUGUGUAUUCCCGGCCUUUAUAAAUGACCCGGUCAAGUUGGUUUCAAAGUCCGACAGGCUUGUCUGUUUACUAGCUGCGUGGCCUUGGACGGGUGGCUGACAUCUGUAAAGAAUCCUCCUGUGAUGAAACUGAGGAAUCGGGUGGCCGGGCAAGCUGGGAAGAGCAAAGCCAGAGCUGCGCUGCCUCAAUACCCACAAAAGACCAUUCCCAGUAUACAUAAGCACAGGAUGUUUUUCUCAAGAGGGAUGUAUUUAUCACUUGGACAUCUGUUUAUAAUAUAAACAGACAUGUGACUGGGAACAUCUUGCUGCCAAAAGAAUCCUAGGCAGUGGCUCAUUGUAUGUGAGGUUGAACCACGUGAAAUUGCCAAUAUUAGGCUGGCUUUUAUCUACAAAGAAGGAGUUUCAUGGGGUUCAGCCUAACAGUUAUGGAAACUACAGUCCUUAUAAACCAUUGGCAUGGUAAUAAACAGAUCUUAAGUAUAAAAAUUUUGUAAUUGGGCCUUUACUCUCUCAAUAAUAAAGUAUUUUGUUUAUAUAAA